CGCCUCGCCGCAGUCGGGGCAGCCGCUCGCCCCUCUUUUCCAUGUAUCCGUCCAGGUGAGAUCCGGCCCCACCGAGACUCGCUCCCCUCUCUGGACAGAGGAUCUCAACUGGGUCCCGGUUUCCCUCUCCGCGCCUCCGCCCAGAGUUGCAUCAUCUGCACCGAAAGGCGGCGAGACAGGGUCUCCCAAGACCCCCGCCCCACCGGCGCCCACGCCUGCGGUCUUGACCGCCCAGAAGAUGGGGGCUGGCCGUGCACGUGGCCCCGGGCUCCCACCCCAGCCCCCGCGCCGGCGGAGUGGACCCCACUGGCGGCGAGUCCUGGAGCGUGGAGCAGGGACGCGGGGUGGGAAUCCGGGGGAGAUGCACGUUUCGGUGCCCAGCAUUGAGUUCGCUGCAUUGUGGAUGGGAAAUGGCUGUUUGCAAAUCGCCCUUUUUGGCGGACCGUGUGGGGUGGCGGUAAACGCUGUCGUUGCGCGGGCGGCACGCGAGGUGGGUGCCCGCUGGGGGAGGGACGCGGGGCUCUGCCCAGGUUGCGUUCGGGGGAUGGAGGUUUUCCUGGGACCUCACUUCCCUGAGCCCCAGGCGAGACCGCAGCUGAGCUGUAGGAUGCAAGCGGGAGGCGGAGCGUGGGUGGGAGAGCGGAGCGCGAAAUUCUCGGCUUCCCGAGGAUCUUCUGGGCUUACUUGUCCCCAGCUUUGUCCCAAAGUGUCGCUUCCGGAGGCGGAGUGGCCGGCGGUUUCCGGGUCUCAGUAGGGUCUGGAUCUCCCACCUGGAAACCUAGAGGAGUUUCCCGCUCUCCGUGCGCGUGGCCUUCCCCAGGCCCCUCCGGGAGUGCUGGCGCGCGAGUGCAGGGGUGCCCCGGGAACGUCGUGACCCCAAGGGGGUCUUGUGGUUUAAGGAGCGAACGGAACCGGCCAGGCGAUGCCAGCUGAACCCGCCUUCCCGGGACGCACGUGCAUCCGGCCGCCCGGCGCUGUUGUCUUGGGGAGCCCGCGGGUUCGGGUCUGGGUCGCCUGGCGAGCUUUCCGCCGAGCGCCUCUGAGUUCUACAGAGCCCCGACGGCUUGCGAUCUGCGUUCCCGGCAGUCCCUUACCUUGCGAGAGAGGGCUCCAGGGCGAGGCGAGGGGCCAAAAGCAAGGCGCUGGGCCGCCUGCGUCUGCCGGGGCCUCGGGUCCACGGCUUUCUGGAAGAUUCGGCGGCGGAGCAUGCGCGCCCCAGGCCAGACAGGGCCUGUGCCAGACGGAGAGUCCCUUCCCGUAGGUGACUCCCGCGACCCGCGGAGGAAGGUGCUGCUCCGCUCACGGCGGCGGCUUCUUACAAGGAUCCCAUGACAGAUUCUGUUGUCACGUCUCCUUACAGAGUUUGAGCGGUGCUGAACUGUCAGCACCAUCUGUCCGGUCCCAGCAUGCCUUCUGAGACCCCCCAGGCAGAAGUGGGGCCCACAGGCUGCCCCCACCGCUCAGGGCCACACUCGGCGAAGGGGAGCCUGGAGAAGGGGUCCCCAGAGGAUAAGGAAGCCAAGGAGCCCCUGUGGAUCCGGCCCGAUGCUCCGAGCAGGUGCACCUGGCAGCUGGGCCGGCCUGCCUCCGAGUCCCCACAUCACCACACUGCCCCGGCAAAAUCUCCAAAAAUCUUGCCAGAUAUUCUGAAGAAAAUCGGGGACACCCCUAUGGUCAGAAUCAACAAGAUUGGGAAGAAGUUCGGCCUGAAGUGUGAGCUCUUGGCCAAGUGUGAGUUCUUCAACGCGGGCGGGAGCGUGAAGGACCGCAUCAGCCUGCGGAUGAUUGAGGAUGCUGAGCGCGACGGGACGCUGAAGCCCGGGGACACGAUUAUCGAGCCGACAUCCGGGAACACCGGGAUCGGGCUGGCCCUGGCUGCGGCAGUGAGGGGCUAUCGCUGCAUCAUCGUGAUGCCAGAGAAGAUGAGCUCCGAGAAGGUGGACGUGCUGCGGGCACUGGGGGCUGAGAUUGUGAGGACGCCCACCAAUGCCAGGUUCGACUCCCCGGAGUCACACGUGGGGGUGGCCUGGCGGCUGAAGAACGAAAUCCCCAAUUCUCACAUCCUAGACCAGUACCGCAACGCCAGCAACCCCCUGGCUCACUAUGACACCACCGCUGAUGAGAUCCUGCAGCAGUGUGAUGGGAAGCUGGACAUGCUGGUGGCUUCAGUGGGCACGGGCGGCACCAUCACGGGCAUUGCCAGGAAGCUGAAGGAGAAGUGUCCUGGAUGCAGGAUCAUUGGGGUGGAUCCCGAAGGGUCCAUCCUCGCAGAGCCGGAGGAGCUGAACCAGACGGAGCAGACAACCUACGAGGUGGAAGGGAUCGGCUACGACUUCAUCCCCACGGUGCUGGACAGGACGGUGGUGGACAAGUGGUUCAAGAGCAACGAUGAGGAGGCGUUCACCUUUGCCCGCAUGCUGAUCGCGCAAGAGGGGCUGCUGUGCGGUGGCAGUGCUGGCAGCACGGUGGCGGUGGCCGUGAAGGCCGCGCAGGAGCUGCAGGAGGGCCAGCGCUGCGUGGUCAUUCUGCCCGACUCAGUGCGGAACUACAUGACCAAGUUCCUGAGCGACAGGUGGAUGCUGCAGAAGGGCUUUCUGAAGGAGGAGGACCUCACGGAGAAGAAGCCCUGGUGGUGGCACCUCCGUGUUCAGGAGCUGGGCCUGUCAGCCCCGCUGACCGUGCUCCCGACCAUCACCUGUGGGCACACCAUCGAGAUCCUCCGGGAGAAGGGCUUCGACCAGGCGCCCGUGGUGGAUGAGGCGGGGGUAAUCCUGGGAAUGGUGACGCUUGGGAACAUGCUCUCGUCCCUGCUUGCCGGGAAGGUGCAGCCGUCAGACCAAGUUGGCAAAGUCAUCUACAAGCAGUUCAAACAGAUCCGCCUCACGGACACGCUGGGCAGGCUCUCGCACAUCCUGGAGAUGGACCACUUCGCCCUGGUGGUGCACGAGCAGAUCCAGUCGCAGGACCAGGCCUGGGCAGGCGUGGUGGGGGGGCCUGCAGACCACAGCACCGGGAAGUCCAGUCAGCGGCAGAUGGUGUUCGGGGUGGUCACCGCCAUUGACUUGCUGAACUUCGUGGCCGCCCAGGAGCGGGACCAGAAGUGAAGUCCGGAGCGCUGGGCGGUGCGGAGCGGGCCCGCCACCCUUGCCCACUUCUCCUUCGCUUUCCUGAGCCCUAAACACACGCGUGAUUGGUAACUGCCUGGCCUGGCACCGUUAUCCCUGCACACGGCACAGAGCAUCCGUCUCCCCUCGUUAACACAUGGCUUCCUAAAUGGCCCUGUUUACGGCCUAUGAGAUGAAAUAUGUGAUUUUCUCUAAUGUAACUUCCUCUUAGGAUGUUUCACCAAGGAAAUAUUGAGAGAGAAGUCGGCCAGGUAGGAUGAACACAGGCAAUGACUGCGCAGAGUGGAUUAAAGGCAAAAGAGAGAAGAGUCCAGGAAGGGGCGGGGAGAAGCCUGGGUGGCUCAGCAUCCUCCACGGGCUGCGCCGUCUGCUCGGGGCUGAGCUGGCGGGAGCAGUUUGCGUGUUUGGGUUUUUUAAUUGAGAUGAAAUUCAAAUAACCUAAAAAUCAAUCACUUGAAAGUGAACAAUCAGCGGCAUUUAGUACAUCCAGAAAGUUGUGUAGGCACCACCUCUGUCACGUUCUGGAACAUUCUGUCAUCACCCCGUGAAGCAAUCAUUUCCCCUCCCGUCUUCCUCCUCCCCUGGCAACUGCUGAUCGACUUUGUGUCUCUGUUGUCUAAAAUAGGUUUUCCCUGUUCUGGACAUUUCAUAUAAAUGGAAUCACACAA